AGCCUGGAAGGGAAAGGACAGCGGAGAGCAGGGCAGAGCCUGAGCAGGCAGGGCACCUCCAGGUGGGCAGGAGCUACCACUCAGCACCAUGAGCACCGCCACAGGCCCAGAAGCUGCCCCAAAGCCAAGCGCCAAGUCUAUCUAUGAGCAGAGGAAGCGUUACUCCACAGUUGUUAUGGCUGAUGUAUCCCAGUACCCAGUCAAUCACCUGGUGACGUUCUGCCUGGGUGAGGACGAUGGCGUGCAUACCGUGGAGGAUGCCUCCAGGAAGUUGGCCGUCAUGGAUAGCCAGGGCCGAGUCUGGGCACAGGAGAUGCUGCUGCGAGUGUCUCCCGACCAUGUCACGCUGCUCGACCCGGCCUCCAAGGAGGAGCUGGAGUCGUACCCACUGGGCGCCAUCGUGCGCUGUGACGCGGUGAUGCCACCCGGCAGGAGCCGCUCGUUGCUGCUGCUCGUGUGCCAGGAACCCGAGCGCGCGCAGCCCGACGUGCACUUCUUCCAGGGCCUGCGCCUCGGGGCGGAGCUGAUCCGAGAGGACAUCCAGGGGGCUCUGCACAAUUACCGCUCGGGCCGCGGGGAGCGCAGGGCGGCGGCGCUCAGGGCCACGCAGGAGGAGUUGCAGCGCGACCGCUCGCCCGCCGCUGAGACCCCGCCCCUGCAGCGCCGCCCGUCAGUCCGCGCAGUGAUCAGCACCGUAGAGCGGGGCGCGGGCCGCGGACGACCCCAGGCGAAGCCCAUUCCCGAGGCAGAGGAGGCGCAGAGGCCUGAGCCGGUGGGGACCUCGAGCAACGCUGACUCGGCCUCCCCGGACCUGGGUCCCCGGGGUCCUGACCUGGCGGUUCUGCAGGCGGAGCGGGAAGUGGACAUCCUGAACCACGUGUUCGACGACGUAGAGAGCUUUGUAUCGAGGCUGCAGAAGUCGGCGGAGGCGGCCAGGGUGCUGGAGCACCGGGAACGCGGCCGCAGGAGCCGGCGCCGGGCGGCUGGGGAGGGCUUGCUGACGCUGCGGGCCAAGCCGCCCUCGGAGGCCGAGUACACCGACGUGCUGCAGAAGAUCAAGUACGCCUUCAGCCUGCUGGCCCGGCUGCGCGGCAACAUCGCCGACCCCUCCUCUCCGGAGCUGUUGCACUUCCUUUUCGGGCCUCUGCAGAUGAUUGUGAACACGUCGGGGGGGCCGGAGUUCGCGAGCAGUGUGCGGCGGCCGCAUCUGACAUCGGAUGCCGUGGCGCUGCUGCGGGACAACGUCACUCCACGUGAAAACGAGCUCUGGACCUCGCUGGGGGACUCGUGGACCCGCCCCGGGCUGGAGCUGUCCCCGGAGGAGGGACCCCCAUACAGACCCGAGUUCUUCAGCGGCUGGGAGCCGCCGGUCACUGACCCGCAGAGCCGCGCCUGGGAGGACCCAGUUGAGAAACAGCUACAGCACGAGCGGAGGCGCCGGCAGCAAAGCGCCCCCCAGGUCGCUGUCAAUGG